AGUCAGGGCUUCUGCUGGGCAGGGCCGGCUGUUAAUCUCGCCUGGCGGAGCGGACACCGGGGCGUGGUGGGGGAGAUGGGCCUUAUAGGUGGCGUCCGCUGGUGAGAAACACCUUGCGCAGGUAAAAGGGUGGCGGCGAGAGGGAGUUCCCACCCGUGGCUUUCUUAGAGAAAUGAAGUCUUAAGUCUUAAAUAGACAACAAGGAGGGGCCGAUCGGUGUCUUUUGGACGCGUCUGGAGCCCCUCCCUCCGCCAAAGGAAAAGCCCCUUGGAUGAGAGGCAGGCGCUUCAGAGAAGCUAAGAAAAGCACCUCUCCGCGCGCCCCACCUCCUCCGCCUCGCGCUCCUCCUGAGCAGCGGGCCCAGACUGCGCUCCGGCCGCGGCCCUCGCCCCGCGGAGCCCUCCUACCCCGGCCCGACGCUCGGCCCGCGACCUGCCCCGAGCCCUCUCCAUGGAGGCAGCCCGCCCCUCCGGCUCCUGGAACGGAGCCCUCUGCCGGCUGCUCCUGCUGACCCUCGCGAUCUUAAUAUUUGCCAGUGAUGCCUGCAAAAAUGUGACAUUACAUGUUCCCUCCAAACUAGAUGCCGAGAAACUUGUUGGUAGAGUUAACCUGAAAGAGUGCUUUACAGCUGCAAAUCUAAUUCAUUCAAGUGAUCCUGACUUCCAAAUUUUGGAGGAUGGUUCAGUCUAUACAACAAAUACUAUUCUAUUGUCCUCGGAGAAGAGAAGUUUUACCAUAUUACUUUCCAACACUGAGAACCAAGAAAAGAAGAAAAUAUUUGUCUUUUUGGAGCAUCAAACAAAGGUCCUAAAGAAAAGACAUACUAAAGAAAAAGUUCUAAGGCGCGCCAAGAGAAGAUGGGCUCCAAUUCCUUGUUCGAUGCUAGAAAACUCCUUGGGUCCUUUUCCACUUUUCCUUCAACAGGUUCAAUCUGACACGGCCCAAAACUAUACCAUAUACUAUUCCAUAAGAGGUCCUGGAGUUGACCAAGAACCUCGGAAUUUAUUUUAUGUGGAGAGAGACACUGGAAACUUGUAUUGUACUCGUCCUGUAGAUCGUGAGCAGUAUGAAUCUUUUGAGAUAAUUGCCUUUGCAACAACUCCAGAUGGGUAUACUCCAGAACUUCCACUGCCCCUAAUAAUCAAAAUAGAGGAUGAAAAUGAUAACUACCCAAUUUUUACAGAAGAAACUUAUACUUUUACAAUUUUUGAAAAUUGCAGAGUGGGCACUACUGUGGGACAAGUGUGUGCUACUGACAAAGAUGAGCCUGACACGAUGCACACACGCCUGAAGUACUCCAUCAUUGGGCAGGUGCCACCAUCACCCACCCUAUUUUCUAUGCAUCCAACUACAGGCGUGAUCACCACAACAUCAUCUCAGCUAGACAGAGAGUUAAUUGACAAGUACCAGUUGAAAAUAAAAGUACAAGACAUGGAUGGUCAGUAUUUUGGUCUACAGACAACUUCAACUUGUAUCAUUAACAUUGAUGAUGUAAAUGACCACUUGCCAACAUUUACUCGUACUUCUUAUGUGACAUCAGUGGAAGAAAAUACAGUUGAUGUGGAAAUCUUACGAGUUACUGUUGAGGAUAAGGACUUAGUGAAUACUGCUAACUGGAGAGCUAAUUAUACCAUUUUAAAGGGCAAUGAAAAUGGCAAUUUUAAAAUUGUAACAGAUGCCAAAACCAAUGAAGGAGUUCUUUGUGUAGUUAAGCCUUUGAAUUAUGAAGAAAAGCAACAGAUGAUCUUGCAAAUUGGUGUAGUUAAUGAAGCUCCAUUUUCCAGAGAGGCUAGUCCAAGAUCAGCCAUGAGCACAGCAACAGUUACUGUUAAUGUAGAAGAUCAGGAUGAGGGCCCUGAGUGUAACCCUCCAAUACAGACUGUUCGCAUGAAAGAAAAUGCAGAAGUGGGAACAACAAGCAAUGGAUAUAAAGCAUAUGACCCAGAAACAAGAAGUAGCAGUGGCAUAAGGUAUAAGAAAUUAACUGAUCCAACAGGGUGGGUCACCAUUGAUGAAAAUACAGGAUCAAUCAAAGUUUUCAGAAGCCUGGAUAGAGAGGCAGAGACCAUCAAAAAUGGCAUAUAUAAUAUUACAGUCCUUGCAUCAGACCAAGGAGGGAGAACAUGUACGGGGACACUGGGCAUUAUACUUCAAGACGUGAAUGAUAACAGCCCAUUCAUACCUAAAAAGACAGUGAUCAUCUGCAAACCCACCAUGUCAUCUGCGGAGAUUGUUGCGGUUGAUCCUGAUGAGCCUAUCCAUGGCCCACCCUUUGACUUUAGUCUGGAGAGUUCUACUUCAGAAGUACAGAGAAUGUGGAGACUGAAAGCAAUUAAUGAUACAGCAGCACGUCUUUCCUAUCAGAAUGAUCCUCCAUUUGGCUCAUAUGUAGUACCUAUAACAGUGAGAGAUAGACUUGGCAUGUCUAGUGUCACUUCAUUGGAUGUUACACUGUGUGACUGCAUUACCGAAAAUGACUGCACACAUCGUGUAGAUCCAAGGAUUGGCGGUGGAGGAGUACAACUUGGAAAGUGGGCCAUCCUUGCAAUAUUGUUGGGCAUAGCAUUGCUCUUUUGCAUCCUGUUUACGCUGGUCUGUGGGGCUUCUGGGACGUCUAAACAACCAAAAGUAAUUCCUGAUGAUUUAGCCCAGCAGAACCUAAUUGUAUCAAACACAGAAGCUCCUGGAGAUGACAAAGUGUAUUCUGCGAAUGGCUUCACAACCCAAACUGUGGGCGCUUCUGCUCAGGGAGUUUGUGGCACCGUGGGAUCAGGAAUCAAAAACGGAGGUCAGGAGACCAUCGAAAUGGUGAAAGGAGGACACCAGACCUCGGAAUCCUGCCGGGGGGCUGGCCACCAUCACACCCUGGACUCCUGCAGGGGAGGACACACGGAGGUGGACAACUGCAGAUACACUUACUCGGAGUGGCACAGUUUUACUCAGCCCCGUCUUGGUGAAGAAUCCAUUAGAGGACACACUCUGAUUAAAAAUUAAACAAUGAAAGAAAGUGUAUCUGUGUAAUCAAGAUGAAAAUCACAAGCAUGCCCAAGACUAUGUCCUGACAUAUAACUAUGAAGGAAGAGGAUCGGUGGCUGGGUCUGUAGGUUGUUGCAGUGAACGACAAGAAGAAGAUGGGCUUGAAUUUUUGGAUAAUUUGGAGCCCAAAUUUAGGACACUAGCAGAAGCAUGCAUGAAGAGAUGAGUGUGUUCUAAUAAGUCUCUGAAAGCCAGUGGCUUUAUGACUUUUAAAAAAAAUUACAAACCAAGAAUUUUUUAAAGCAGAAGAUGCUAUUUGUGGGGGUUUUUCUCUCAUUAUUUGGAUGGAAUCUCUUUGGUCAAAUGCACAUUUACAGAGAGACACUAUAAACAAGUACACAAAUUUUUCAAUUUUUACAUAUUUUUAAAUUACUUAUCUUCUAUCCAAGGAGGUCUACAGAGAAAUUAAAGUCUGCCUUAUUUGUUACAUUUGGGUAUAAUGACAACAGCCAAUUUAUAGUGCAAUAAAAUGUAAUUAAUUCAAGUCCUUAUUAUAGACUAUUUGAAGCACAACCUAAUGGAAAAUUGUAGAGACCUUGCUUUAACAUUAUCUCCAGUUAAUUAAGUGUUCAUGUGGUGCUUGGAAACUGUUGUUUUCCUGAACAUCUAAAGUGUGUAGACUGCAUUCUUGCUAUUAUUUUAUUCUUGUAAUGUGACCUUUUCACUGUGCAAAGGGAGAUUUCUAGCCAGGCAUUGACUAUUACAAUUUCAUUUUGGUGGAGUUUAGUUUUAGGUUUUAUUGUAUAUAAAAUCCUGCACUGAAUCUGUGUCUCCUCUGUUACCUACUUUUGCCAGUGAAAUUUAAGUUUUAAAAUACUUUCAGAAUGUAUUUUUACUACUGCAAGUUUUUGGUCUUUAAAAUGUCAAGUAGCAUCUCUCUCUUUCUCUCUGUCUCUUUCUGUUUCUCUCUCCAGUUUUUUUUUUUUUUUUAAUUUCCAUAUGGGCUAAAGAAUCCAAAUAUUUUAAAAAUCUGUCUCUCUUUUCUUCUCUCAUAAAGUGAAUUAUUCCUUUUUUUUGUUUUAUGUAAGUGUAUAUAUUCUUAGUUUUUCUUGAAAUCAUUGUAAUGUUAACUUUGUUGUUUCAAAUAUCUUGGUGAUUGCUUCAUUAUCUCUUCAACAAAAAAAACCUUUAAUUUUGCCAUUGAAACUGUAGAACUAUGCCAUGCUUUUAUUAGAAGCAGUGCUCUGUGUUAACAACAAGAAUGGUGUAAUUAGAAUUGGGAUGUGGAUAUUUACUGUAUGACAACACAUUUACAGUUCUGUAAUGCAAGGAUGCAGUUUAAAAAUGUGAAGUAGUGAUGGUUUUUGAAAUAAGCUUUAAAAUAUAGGGAUCUUGAAGGCUCCCUGGGGUAACUAUUUUAUAACUUAGAUAAAAUGGCUAGUCAUAUCUGUGUGUUUGUAAAGUUAUUUUUUUAAUAUUUUAAGAUUACAAUUUUAACAAAUGUAGAAAUGAGCCAAACUAUUUAAAUUUUAAAACAGUAAAACAAAAUGAAACUUAAUAGCUCACAAAAUUCCAGUCCAUGUUUCAUGACUUAUUUUAGUCAAUGAAUUUUCUAUUUAUACUAAACAUAUGGACAUUUUAAAUGUGUUUCUAAUAUUUUUGAUUAUCUAUAAUGUGCCUGUCUUCAAUUCACAAGAUUGGGUUAUAACAAUUAUUUGCCAGAUUAACACUAGGGAAUUAUUUGAUAACCAGCUUAUCUUAUCAGUAGUUUUAUUGCUGAUCAGGCAAAAAUAGUUUUCCAAAGUUAUUUUUAAUAAAGUAUAUACAAAAUUCUUAUAUAUUACUAGUCAUGAUAAAGUAAAUUAAGCAGUUUUUAAAACUUAGUGUGAGUUUGUUCAUCACAGGUCUGAUAUGAGUUUAAGGGAUUUCGCACUCCCUGAAUCAGAGAAGUAAGACCCCUUCCUUAGAUUCCUGUUAUACAUUUUUUAAAAUGUAGAGUUUGUUUUGGAGACAUUUUCAGUGCAUUGUUAUUGCCAUAUUUAUAUAAUAUGACUAUUCUAAAGGCUGUGAGGCCAUGGGGUAUUGGUUAAGUUGCUUGCUUUUGCUUUGUCCAUUUUCAUCAUUUUAAAAUGGGGGAUAAUAACAGAACUUGUUUCCUAGGGCCAUUGUAAGUCACUUGAAUAAAAAAUAGUUUUGAAGCAUGAGAGUCAUACAGAGCGGUCCACCUAAAAGGCACUCCUGAUAAUAAUAAAUGAUUUUAAACAAGUCACAUGUACAAUUCAUUUCAUGUUAACAAAAGGUCAAUUAAGACAAUAAGAUACUGAAAAGAUUUUUCUUUUCACUGUAGAACAUGUCUCUUCAUAAUGAUCACCUGAUGACUGGGUCUUGUAUGUUCAGUUUUUCAGAAUACGUAGUGCAAAGAUUGCUGAGGCAUUCGUAUGGGAUUGCCUGGUUUGAAACACUGUGAAACUGUAAGGUUCAAAUUGGAUGAAAAGCAGAACAUCUGCUUCUUAAAAUGGGCACUAAUUCUAACACCCUAUGAAAAUUAUGUGUAUUUUAGAUUCUCCCUGUCAAUCCCUUCCUUGGCUUCUUCCCUAGCUGUCCAGCUAGACAUUAGCAGUCACUUGCCUGGGAGGUCAUGGCUGUUUGGCAGUCGUCAUAGUAACCCCAAGUGCUAAGACUUCCAAGUAAGAGUGUCUUGAUGCAAAUUCCGGCUCUAUCCUUACUAGCUGUGGGAUUUGAGAAGUCACUUAAGCUUUCUGUGCUUAGUUUCCUUACUUAUAGGACCUGUACUGAGGAGGGUAGAGGAGUCUACUUGACAGGGCUUUGUCAGAGUUAAUUCAUGAAAAGAGUUGGCAUAGAGUUAGCACUCAAUCAUGUACCUUAGCCACUGCUAUUGUUCUAUGAGCAGAGAACGCCUGAGUUGGGAACAAUUUAGCUUCAGUCUCCACUCUGCUUUACUGCUGACAUCUUGCCAUGAUGCUCUUAUUCACCUUUCCCAGAAGCCCGACCAGUAUUUCACCAGUGAUGGCCUUUGGGAAUUUCAUGGCUCAUAGUAGCUUCCAGGUCUCUCAUUUGUGGUAUUCAGCAAGUUACAUCUUAUUCAUCCCUAGCCAGAAGUCAGUGUGAUAAAUCUUGAUGCUUAACUGAAAAGGCAGGUAAAAUUCUCGAGGAGGCAAAAUCAUAAAGAGUUUCCCGAAGAAAUGGCUGGUGCUUCUUCAGCAAAUGAAAAGCAGCAAGAUCUUCUGUUCCAUGCAGUGUGUGUCUGGGGGCUCCUGGUAAUCAUUACUUUUUCUUUAUUCCCAUCUUAAGACUGUUUUUAUCUUGGAUCCCAAUUCUGUUUUGCCAAAUCUGACUUUGACUACGGGCUUCCCUUUUGUCUCCAUCUCCAUUCCUGGACUCCAGAUUGAAGUCUUGACAACUGACUUUGCUCUGAUCAGCCCCUUUAGUAUCAUCUCCAAAAUAAAAUGCUUUCCCUUCUUUGUGCCUAGAAUCAUCUUGUUUUUCACCUCCUUAAAUAUUCAAAGCCCUAAGAAGUUACCUGAUAUCCGUAUAAACCUACAGCUCUUAUAUCAGCUCCCCUGCGAGCCCCCUGUUAACCUAGCACUUCAAACUCAUGCAAAAAGACAAACACAUACUACCACAUCAAAUCAGGUUCUCCUGAGUUAUUUACACAAUGGUGCCCUUCUUCCACUUACUUAGGCUUGAAACAGAGAAUCCUUGAUUCCUCUCUCUUCUUUCCAUAGCAUCCUCUAUUUUUUGCCAAAAACUGCCAAACUUUUGAGAAUUGUAGACACAAUUUCAUUCAUUAAAUACUUUGUUUGUACUGUAGUCAUUUGAUGCCUUCCCAGUGCAGUCAUAUGUAGCCUUUUAAAACAGAGACUAGAAGGACUGUGCUUCUAUGAGAAAGUGCAAGAUGAAUCAGCCACUCUCCCCACCCACACACUUGAAUGCAAGUCAAGACACGGUGGAUGUAAGGAGUGGGCUAAUGCCUGUAAAACACAUCACACAAUGCCUGGCACAUAGUAAGUGCAUAAUGCAUGUUUUUAAAAAGCUUCAGAUGAUGUGAAAGAACUUCAGGACACUAGUGAGUGAACUUCUGCUUCUGCUACUCCCAAUCCAAGCAUUCAUGAGGUUGAGGUGUACCCUAUGUCAGCUGUUCCCACUCUUCACUUCAUUCCUGAUCAAUAUUCCCCCCCGCCAGUACCCCAGAUUAAAUCUUCAGCAUCACUCAGCUCCAAUGGUGUUUAUGCUUCCAAUUUCUUCCCUCUUCUCUUUUUUCAAGGGCCAUCAAAGAGCAGAUAUGAUCAUGCCAUUCUGCCUAAGAGCUUUCUAUAGGGUUUUAGAGGAUAAAUUCUAAACACAAAAUCACUUUUAAAUACAGAUGCUUCUUGACUUAUGAUGGGGUUACAUCCUGAUAAACCCAUGGUAAAUUGAAAAUAUUACAAAUCAAAACAGCAUUUUCCAUUUACCAUAUGUUCAACUUAAAAUAAGCUUAUUGGGAUGUAGUCUCAUAAGUGUAGGAGAAUGCUGAAUGCAUAUUUCUUUGACACCAUCAUAAAGUUGAAAUAUCAGAUCGAGCCAUCUUAAGUUGAGGACCUUCUGUACUAAUUUCCCCAAUCUCCUUGUAUCCUUCAUUUUUCAAUUUGUGCCUUGCUCAUGAUUAGUUCUCUUUUUACAAUGUCUUUACUCAUUGUCUCUUUCUUUGUAAAAAUAUUACUUUUUGAGGAUCUAGUAAAAAUACUACCGCCUAGACAUUUGUGUGUCUAGAGCACAUGGCUGUAAAGUUUUCAUCUACAGGUUUGUGUGUGUGUUUCUUUUCUUUCAUGUAGGACACUAAGGACCAAGAAAGGUGUUCACAAUUGCAUGCCUAUACAACUCUGGCCAUUAAUUUUUUUUUUUUUUUUUUUGAGACGGAAUCUCACUCUGUCACCUAGGCUGGAGUGCAGUGGCAUGAUCAUGGCUCACUGCAACCUCUGCCUCCCAGGUUCAAGCAAUUCUUCUGCCUCAGCCUCCUGAGUAGCUGGGAUUACAGGCACCUACCACCACGCCUGGUUAAUUUUUGUAUUUUUAGCAGAGAAAGGGUUUCACCAUGUUGGCCAGGCUGGUCUUGAACUCCUGACCUCAAGUGAUCUGUCAGCACUUGGCCUCCCAAAGUGCUGGGAUUACAGGCAUAAGCCACUGUGCCUGGCCAAAUUUUGAUUCAUCAAAUUAUAUUGCCCAGGUCAUAAAGGAAAAAAGAGAAAUAAUAAAAGUUAGGUUUUUUAUUCUCAGCACAUACUAAUUUUCUGUGGCAUAAAUUUUACAUGAUAGACAUGGUGUAUGUUAGAUUCUGCACUGAAUUGUUUUUCCUCAGAAGACAUUGAAUGACUAGAACAAUUGUUUGCAUUCACAGCUUAAUACAGGAAAGUGAAGUGUUGAGAUUUUGGAAUCCCUUCUCCCUUGGGAUAGUGAGAGGGGCAGACAGAAGGGGUAGUGUCUGAAUAUUGUGGUUCAGGCCAGCUCAAAUCCUACCACCAAUAAUUGCACGAACCUACUUGUAGCCACCAAUAAUUGCCCCAUAUUGAAAUGUAACCCCCAAGGGUUCUCCUCUGUCUUCUUGACCACUGUAUGCCUAACAUGUAGAGCAGUAGACACUGAAUAUAUUUGGUGUGUGAUGAAUAAAUGGAUGAAUGAAUAAAUGCACAUGUGUGUUAGGUACCUGGCUAAGAUCAGACUGCAUAUUGCCUAAAGAAUUCUUUUUCUCAACUUGAAAAUUUUUAGCCAAUGUGAAAAUUAUGUUUGCGACUGUCACUUCAUCAUUGCCAGGUUCAAACACUGCAGUGAAUUUUUUUUUUUUAACCAAAAGGCCACUCUCUAACCACCUGAGGAAAAGCAACUAAAAACCACUUAUGUUUAGAAAUUCAAGAAAUGAUUCUUAUGAGUUUGCCAAAAUUCCCAUUAGUUAUUUAUAAAAUGUUGUAAGUCAGGCCUUGCUUCAAAAAAUAUCUUGAGAAACCACAAAGCAAAGAAAGUGGCAUACAUCUACGAGCUUUUUCCAUGUUAGGCUGGGAGAACAUUCUGUAACAGGAAACCACCGUGCUCAUGUGUGCCCUGAGAGAAGAAAAUCUUCACACAAGAAGUAGAGAAUAGGGAAAGAAAUGCAUAGCAAUGAGCCUCAGAGGCAAUGCCUAUAUUGUGCUGUGAACUGAUAAUGUCACUUGGAAGAUAACACGUAAGAGGUAGUUCCCAGCCCUGCUCUUCUCACGUAGGACAUGUAGGACAGACCUAUGUGUUUUGCUUUCUGGGGAGAGGGGAUCAGUUGUAUGACCCCCUUUAUUAUUUCCUCUUCACCAGUUCUGGUUUUCUAGGUUUGAGGACUGAAAUCUUGAGAAGUAGGAUCUGAUCUUUCUUCCAAGAAGCUCUUCUCUCCCCACCUGUCCUUGUGUUCUUUAUCCCAUCAAUAGCUAAGAAGCAGAACCUAUUACUUUUGCUUAAAUGUUUUAAAUUAAGCAAAUAGAUACAUUAUGAGGCUGCAUUUUAAACUUUAGAUAUUUCAAAUAAGACAUGCAAUAUAGAGUCUUAAGGUAAAACAAAAGAGCAUAAUGCUAAAAAACAGGCAACAAAAAGAAGCUAGAGCUUUGAAAUAGCUAGUCAGGUAAACAGAGCACUUUAAUUUAAAAGAACACACCCUAAAUCUUGUUUUAUAGAGGAAUUUUACUGUGUCAUGGAUUUGGAGCAUAUUCUUCUCAAGCCAUUUGGUAUAUCCUAAAUUCUAGGUAUACGUGAGAUUAAAGAAGAGAUACUCACUGAUGUGCCUCCGUAUGGAGUGAUAGUUGGUGCAUGGGAAAUGGCAAGGGCUGUUUUGUUUCAUUCUCUCUUCCCUUUGUGACUGUACCUUUGUAUCCCUACAGAAAAUCUGGGCAUAGCUGAGAGGUUAGAAUUGUGGAGUUUCUGCUAGCCACAUCUUUUCUGUUUACUUAUUUUGUUAGGAUUCAAGGGAGAGGACAGAGCAGAACACUCACUGCUUUUCAGUUAACAAAUAUGAAGGCAAACUUGCUGAUAUAUUCGCUUGUAUAAUUUUUAGAGUGUGUUUCACUGACCAUCAGCAUCAGAAUCACCCUGGUGUUGCUGAAAAUAGAGAUCCCUCAUGAAUCAGUCACAGGAGUAACAGGCUAGUAGGGGAAAAGUAUAGAAGCCUUCACUUUUCAAUACAUUUUCUAGGUCAUUUUUUCUUACUCUAAAGUUUGACAAUCGUUAGGGUUUUAGUAACUGGGUUUAUUGAUUAUUUGGUGGUUUAUGAAACUUAAGUAUUUAAAAUUUGCCUUUUCAUAUAAAACAUAUUAAGCAAAAUGCUAGAAAUGUACCAAAGAGUUGAAACACAUUGAUGAGUAAAAUUUCACAAUGUCUGCAAAUUAAGCAUUUCAGAAUGUACAUUGUUCCCUGUGGUUUCUACUUUCUACAUGCAUGUGAACGAGAGAAAUAGUCUUAAGGUAGGAAUGCAGAACAAAGCCACACAGAAAACAUUUAAUAAAAAUUAACAAGUUUUGCCACAUAAAUGCUGCUAGUCAAGAAGAUGUAUGCAAAGUAAGUUGCAUAUAUUUUUAAAAAUCAGAAUUGCCAAAUCUCCAGAGAUAAAUAGAACUAGAAAGGUCAACAGCAGGUGGAACAAGUGACUGUCCAGAAGGCAGCAACUGUUUGGCAUCACUGUGCUGUUGUGUGGGGACCUGUGUCAGGUGGGGUAACAGGUAAUGCUCACUGACUGUGGCGGCCAGGAGCUUCAGAGGGGCCUGUGAAUCAGGGAUGGGAGAUGAGGGUAGAGACGAGACUUUUCAGCUUAAGGAGUGUUCCCCUGGGAACAGGGCCAAUUGGAAAACUCCCAGGCACCAAGGACAUGAGUUAACCAAUAGGGAAUGAGAGGCUCAGAAAGCCAGAGGUGAAAGGAGCAGAGGGUGUCAAUAUACACAAGAUGUGAUGCAGAAUUACCAAUGAAAUCAAGUAAAAGGGAUUUAUCCAAAAGAAGUAAGAGAAUAGUGUAAAGAUUCUACUCACAUGCAAGGAUGUUUGUCUCAGUGGCAUUAAAUAUAUGAAUAACUGAAAAUAAACUAAAUGUUCCAUGACAGGGAAGUAAUUAAAUGAUGUAUGAUCCAUUACUGUGAUACAAUGUACCAUAAUUGAGGACAAUGGAAACAAUGAUCACACACAGACUUCGCAGUCAGAAAGACGUGGAUCCAAAUCUCAGCUUUGUUCUUGCUGUGUUACCUUGGGAAAUCACAGAAACCUCAAAUUUCUAGCAUAUCAAAUAAGGACAAAUUAGGAAUAAAUUAUAUAAUUCACAUAAAGAUCCUAGCUUACUGCUUGGCUCAUCAGUAUAUCAAUAACCAGCAGCUAUCACUAUUGUGAUAUGAUGAUGGAAUAUCAUGCAAUCAUUUUAUUUUGAAAACUUUAAUUAAAUGGGAAAAGACAUAAACUAUAGUAGUAUUUUAAAACUAGGAUAGGUUUCCAAAUUAUUAUAAUCUCACAUUUAAAUAAAUAUGAGACUAUCUGUAAUACACUAAGAUAUUGAGUGAUAAAUCCUCGGUAAAUGAAAUAUUUAUUCAUUGUGUGUUUCCAUGUUUUCAUUUUACCACAAGCAUUUAUAAUUUAUAACAUUGAGGGAAAAGUUCAUGUAAAUGAAAUACAGAGCAAGAAAAACUCACAGGCUUUAGAAUUUGGGGAGCUUACAGGCCUGUGAAGAAAAGCCUUUUCAUCUUAGCUUUAAUAAAUAAAGUUUUCACUGAACAUAUUAUAUUUACAGUAAAUGAUUAAAUUGAAAGCAAAAAGAAAAUACUGUAUCAUCUCACAUUAUCAUAACUGAGUGCAUUCAUGUGCUUUUGGUCUUAAAAUUUUACUUUAACGCACUUAGGAUUUGUCGUCAGUAAUUUGUUAUGCACUAUCUAGACUAAGAAUAGGUAUUAAUUUACUAGAAUUGUCAAAUGAAAUAUUUCAAGCAAAGUUUGCAUAAUGAAUGCAAGUUUAAACCAAUUAAAUGUGUUCACUUUUUAGCAAGCUAAGCUGCUCCUUAUUUCUCCUGUAGUAGACACAAUCACAGUUAAUCUUUGCACAAUGCAUCGCAUUCUCCAUGCAACCUAACAGAGCGGUCUGGGAUAGAGCCUGAACUUUGGGUCCCUUGGGGCCCAACAGGCAAGGUUCAGAUCUGGGCUCUACCACAAACCAUCUGUGUAACCUGAACCUCCCUAGUCUUCAGUUUCCUCAUCUGCUUUAAAAAAUUGCUAGAACAUAGUUCUAUGUAAAUGUUCGGUGUUAAAAUUUAUUUGGUAUCUACUGUAUGUAAGAUAUGGCCUCUGCUCUCAAAAAUAUGUAGUCCCAGAAGUGAUAUAAUAUGUUCACGGAGACGUACUAUUAAAAAGUGCCACAAAAAA